UUUUUUUUUUUUUUUUUUUUUUUUUGAGACAGUGUCUCGCUCUGUCGCCCAGGCUGGAGUACAGUAGCGCGAUCUCAGCUCACUGCAAUCUCCCCUUCCCAGGUUCAAGCAGUUCUCCUGUCUCAGCCUCCUGAGUAGCUGGGAUCACAGGCGCCACCACCAUGCCUGGCUAAUUUUUUGUAUUUUUAGUAGAGACAGGGUUUUACCACGUUGACCAGCCUUGUCUUGAACUCCUGGCCUCAGGCAAUCCACCUGCCUUGGCCUCCCGAAGUGCUGGGAUUACAGGCAUGAGCCACUGCACCUGGCCUUAUAGAUAUUUUGAAAGAUUAUAUUUCUUAUAUUAAAUAGAGAUAGGGUCUUACCAUGUUGCUCAGGCUGGUCUUCCUGGACUCAAGCAAUCCACCUGCCUCAGACACCCAAAGUGCUGAGAUUACAGGUGUUAGCCACCAUGCCUGGCCUAAUACUUAAUUUUUAAAAAACUUUUUCUUUGGAAAUAAUUUUAGACUUCAAAGAGAGUUGCAAAAAUAAUACAAAUAAUAGCCCUAUAAUCUUCACCUAGAUUCCCCAAGUGCAUCUUUUAAAACCACAAUACAGUGAUCAAAUCAGAAAAUCAACAUUGAUAACAAUUAUUAAUACAUUUUGAAUUUAACUAAAUUUCUGUUCAUUUUCUACCUACAGUAGUAAGAAAUGUCUGGGUAACAUCAGUGUCACCGAAGUCUGUAUUGCCCAGAUUGGUCUCAAACUCCUGGGCUCAAGCAGUCUGCCCACCUCGGCCUCCCAAAGUGCUGGGAUUACAGGCCUGAGCCACUGCACCUGGUCUGGACUCAAUUUUAGUUUUUGAGUUUUGCUUUUUUUUUUUAAAGCAGUACUAACUACUUGUAAAGAUGUAUAUUUCAUGACUUUUAUUUAUUGGAGGUCUUCAAAACAGCAAAGAGAAAAUUUAUUUUUAUUUUUAAUUUUAUUUUUGAGAUGCGGUCUUGUUCCAUCCCCAGGCUGGAGUGCAGUAGCGCGAUCUUGGCUCACUGCAACCUCCGCCUCCUGGGUUCAACUGGUUCUCCUGCCUCAACCUCCCGAGUAGCUGGGAUUACAGGUGUGUACCACCAUACCCAGCUAAUUUUUGUAUUUUUAGUAGAAAUGGGGUUUCACCAUAUUGGCCAGGCUGGCCUCAAACUUCUUAUCUCUCGAAGUGCUGCGAUUACAGGCAUGAGUCACCAUGCCCAGCCUGAAAAUUUAUUUUUUUUCCAAAGGAAUAAACUCAUUUUAGCUAUUACCACUUGUACAUCGAAACAAUGUUGUGGAGUUUUACUGAUCUUAUUUUUCCUGUAUAUUGAAAUGUUUUGGUAUUUCAUCAUCCUAGGAAUUAUUUCAUCAUUACUCAUCAAUUCUCAAAUAUGCUAAAGAGGACUAAAAUAAUAUGACAAAGGGAGAAUUAUAGAAUUGCUUAAAAGGAUAUGCAGUAGUGAAAUAAAUCAUUAGUUUUACACUUCAGUUUUUAGAGAUGGGGCCUCGCUUUGUUGCCCAGGCCGAAGGGCAGUGGUAUGAUCAUAGCUCUCUGCAGCCUCAAACUUCUGGGCUCAAGUGAUCAUCCCUCCUAAGCAUCCUCGGUAGCUGGGACUAUAGGUGUGCACCGCAGCCCUUCAGUUUUCUUAUUGCUUUUCCCAAAACUUACAGCAACUUUUUUUUUCUUUUUGGAUACAGGGUCUCACUCUGUCACCCAGGCUGGAGUGCAGUGGCGCAAUCUCAGUUCACUGCAACCUUCGCCUCCCAGACUCAAGCAAUCUCACCUCAGCCCUCCAAGUAGCUGGGACUACAGGCAUGUGCCACCACACCUGGCUAAUUUUUGUAUUUUUUUUGUAGAGAGAACGUUUCGCCAUGUUGUCUAGGCUAGUCUCGAACUCCUGGGCUCAAACAAUCCACCCACCUUAGCCUCCCAAAGUGCUGGGAUUCCAGGCAUGAGCCAGCAUGCCCAGCCUACAGCAUCUUUCAAGAAAGUAUAAAAGAAGUUGGGAGAUACCAUCUUAAACAUUAUGUAAGAUGUUAACAUUUGGAGAAUCUAGGUGAAGGAGUACAUGGUUUUGUAGUGCAUCCCUGAGCAUGAGCACAGAAUGAAGCGGCGUUUGGAUGACCAGGAGUCACCGGUGUAUGCAGCCCAGCAGCGUCGGAUCCCUGGCAGCACAGAGGCUUUUCCUCACCAGCACCGGGUGCUUGCCCCUGCCCCUCCUGUGUAUGAAGCAGUGUCUGAGACCAUGCAGUCAGCUACGGGAAUUCAGUACUCUGUAACACCCAGCUACCAGGUUUCAGCCAUGCCACAGAGCUCCGGCAGUCAUGGGCCCGCUAUAGCAGCAGUUCAUAGCAGCCAUCAUCACCCAACAGCGGUGCAGCCCCACGGAGGCCAGGUGGUCCAGAGUCAUGCUCAUCCAGCCCCACCAGUUGCACCAGUGCAGGGACAGCAGCAAUUUCAGAGGCUGAAGGUGGAGGAUGCGCUAUCUUAUCUUGACCAGGUGAAGCUGCAGUUUGGUAGUCAGCCUCAGGUCUACAAUGAUUUCCUUGACAUCAUGAAGGAAUUUAAAUCUCAGAGCAUCGACACCCCAGGAGUGAUUAGUCGUGUGUCCCAGCUAUUCAAAGGCCACCCCGAUCUGAUAAUGGGAUUCAACACCUUCUUGCCCCCUGGCUACAAAAUUGAGGUGCAAACCAAUGACAUGGUGAAUGUGACAACUCCUGGCCAGGUUCAUCAGAUUCCCACCCAUGGCAUCCAGCCACAGCCUCAACCACCACCCCAACAUCCUUCCCAGCCUUCAGCCCAGUCAGCCCCAGCUCCUGCCCAGCCAGCUCCUCAGCCCCCACCUGCCAAAGUCAGCAAGCCCUCCCAACUGCAAGCACAUACUCCGGCCAGUCAGCAGACUCCCCCACUUCCACCGUAUGCAUCCCCACGUUCUCCGCCGGUCCAGCCUCACACACCAGUGACAAUCUCGUUGGGAACGGCCCCAUCCUUGCAGAACAAUCAACCUGUGGAGUUUAAUCAUGCCAUCAACUAUGUUAAUAAGAUCAAGAACAGAUUUCAGGGCCAACCAGACAUCUACAAAGCAUUCCUGGAGAUUUUGCACACAUAUCAGAAAGAGCAGAGAAAUGCCAAGGAAGCUGGAGGAAACUACACUCCAGCAUUGACAGAGCAGGAGGUGUAUGCCCAGGUUGCUCGUCUCUUUAAAAACCAGGAAGAUUUGUUGUCAGAGUUUGGACAAUUCCUACCAGAUGCCAACAGCUCCGUGCUUUUAAGCAAAACAACUGCUGAGAAGGUUGAUUCUGUGAGAAAUGAUCAUGGAGGCACUGUCAAGAAGCCCCAACUGAACAACAAGCCGCAGAGGCCCAGCCAGAAUGGCUGCCAGAUCCGCAGACAUCCUACAGGAACCACCCCUCCAGUUAAGAAGAAACCCAAACUGCUCAAUCUGAAGGAUUCUUCUAUGGCAGAUGCCAGCAAACAUGGUGGUGGAACAGAAUCGUUAUUUUUUGAUAAGGUCCGAAAGGCUCUUCGGAGUGCAGAAGCCUACGAAAAUUUCCUACGCUGUCUUGUUAUUUUUAACCAGGAGGUGAUCUCUCGUGCUGAGCUUGUGCAACUAGUCUCUCCUUUCCUGGGGAAAUUCCCUGAGUUGUUUAAUUGGUUUAAAAACUUUCUGGGCUAUAAGGAGUCUGUACAUCUGGAAACUUAUCCAAAGGAGCGAGCCACAGAGGGCAUUGCUAUGGAGAUAGAUUAUGCUUCUUGUAAACGAUUGGGCUCCAGCUAUCGAGCCUUACCAAAGAGUUACCAGCAGCCCAAGUGUACAGGACGGACUCCUCUCUGUAAAGAGGUUUUAAAUGAUACCUGGGUUUCCUUCCCUUCGUGGUCUGAGGACUCUACCUUUGUGAGUUCCAAGAAGACUCAAUAUGAAGAACAUAUUUAUCGUUGUGAAGAUGAACGCUUUGAGCUUGAUGUAGUUUUAGAGACCAAUCUGGCAACAAUCCGGGUUCUGGAAGCAAUACAGAAGAAGCUUUCCCGCUUGUCUGCUGAAGAACAAGCCAAAUUUCGCUUGGACAACACCCUUGGGGGCACAUCAGAAGUCAUCCAUAGAAAAGCACUCCAGAGGAUAUAUGCUGAUAAAGCAGCUGACAUCAUUGAUGGUCUGAGAAAGAAUCCCUCCAUUGCUGUUCCAAUUGUCCUUAAAAGGUUGAAGAUGAAAGAGGAAGAAUGGCGAGAAGCUCAGAGAGGCUUUAACAAAGUAUGGCGAGAACAAAAUGAGAAAUACUACUUGAAGUCUCUGGACCACCAGGGGAUCAACUUUAAACAGAAUGACACCAAGGUCCUGAGGUCUAAGAGCUUACUCAAUGAGAUUGAGAGUAUCUAUGAUGAGAGGCAAGAGCAGGCUACGGAGGAGAAUGCUGGUGUACCUGUUGGCCCACACCUCUCACUUGCGUAUGAAGACAAACAAAUACUGGAAGAUGCUGCUGCUCUGAUUAUCCACCAUGUGAAGAGGCAGACAGGCAUUCAGAAGGAGGACAAAUAUAAGAUAAAACAAAUCAUGCAUCAUUUUAUUCCAGAUUUGCUCUUUGCCCAAAGAGGUGAUCUCUCAGAUGUGGAGGAAGAGGAAGAAGAAGAGAUGGAUGUAGAUGAAGCCACAGGGGCAGUUAAGAAGCACAAUGGUGUUGGGGGCAGUCCCCCUAAGUCCAAGUUACUGUUUAGUAACACAGCAGCUCAAAAAUUAAGAGGAAUGGAUGAAGUAUACAACCUCUUCUAUGUCAACAACAACUGGUAUAUUUUUAUGCGACUGCACCAGAUUCUCUGCCUGAGGCUGCUACGGAUUUGUUCCCAAGCCGAACGGCAAAUUGAAGAAGAAAACCGAGAGAGAGAAUGGGAACGGGAAGUGCUGGGCAUAAAGCGAGACAAGAGUGACAGCCCUGCCAUUCAGCUACGUCUCAAAGAACCUAUGGAUGUUGAUGUAGAAGAUUAUUACCCAGCUUUCCUGGACAUGGUGCGGAGCCUGCUGGAUGGCAACAUAGACUCAUCACAGUAUGAAGAUUCACUGAGAGAGAUGUUCACCAUUCAUGCCUACAUUGCCUUUACCAUGGACAAACUGAUCCAGAGCAUUGUCAGACAGCUGCAGCAUAUCGUGAGUGAUGAGAUCUGUGUGCAGGUGACUGACCUUUACCUGGCAGAAAAUAAUAAUGGGGCCACCGGAGGCCAGCUGAACACACAGAACUCAAGGAGCCUCCUGGAGUCAACGUAUCAGCGGAAAGCUGAGCAGCUAAUGUCAGAUGAGAAUUGCUUUAAGCUUAUGUUUAUUCAGAGCCAAGGCCAGGUCCAGCUGACUAUUGAGCUUCUGGACACAGAAGAGGAGAAUUCGGAUGACCCUGUGGAAGCAGAGCGCUGGUCAGACUACGUGGAGCGAUACAUGAAUUCAGAUACUACCUCGCCUGAGCUUCGUGAACAUCUAGCACAGAAACCAGUAUUUCUCCCCAGGAAUCUACGGCGGAUCCGGAAGUGUCAACGUGGUCGAGAGCAGCAGGAAAAGGAAGGGAAGGAAGGAAACAGCAAGAAGACCAUGGAGAAUGUGGAUAGUCUGGAUAAGCUGGAGUGUAGAUUCAAGCUGAAUUCCUACAAGAUGGUGUAUGUGAUCAAAUCAGAGGACUAUAUGUAUCGGAGGACCGCCCUGCUCCGGGCUCAUCAGUCCCAUGAGCGUGUAAGCAAGCGUCUACAUCAGAGAUUCCAGGCCUGGGUAGAUAAAUGGACCAAGGAGCAUGUGCCCCGUGAAAUGGCAGCAGAGACCAGCAAGUGGCUCAUGGGUGAGGGGCUGGAGGGCCUGGUGCCCUGUACCACCACCUGUGAUACAGAGACCCUGCAUUUUGUGAGCAUUAACAAGUAUCGUGUCAAAUACGGCACAGUAUUCAAAGCCCCUUAACUGCAAAGCCAGAGCAGAUAACUUGGGGUGUGUGUGGGGAUGUGUGUGUGGGCCUAUGCACUCACACACUGAAGAAACAAGGAAGAUGCCUUUCAAGCCUCACUGGGCCUCUCUGGGACAUGGCCACCUGACCUGUGUGUGGCUGGUGCAGCCUGGCACCAAGUGGGCUACCUGUUAGGAACAUGAAUACCUUACAAAGCUGAAGCUGGAACUUUUCCCAAAGGGUUUUGGGUAUAGCCUGCCCUGGAGGGGAAGGAAGUCCAUGCAAGCAAAGACAUGCAGUUUGCUUGCACACACCAGCAGAGCUAAGACUGGAGUCUCCUGUGGCCUAACUUUCAAUGAGGGAACCGGAUGCUGUUCACACUUUGACUGGAUGGAGAUGCAUUUACAAAACAGACUGGAGAAGGACUUAAUACUCAGAUGGAUUGGAACUAUCAUGGUCACUGCUCCUCUCCCCUCCCCACAAAAGGAAAAAAAAGCUGGAUUUGAUUUUUUUUUUCUGGUCACUCGAGCACAUCUAAGAUCACCCAUUAGGUUUUAUCUGGGACCUGCAGUUUGGCUUUGGGAUUGAUCAUCUUGUGGAUUUUAUUCCUGACGAUUCCCUUGCUGCCUACCCUUUUCUCUCCUCUGGUUCUCAACCUCAACGAGUUCAAAUCAGUUGUCCUUUUUAGCUCCCGUGGAACUGUUUUGUAUCUGCCUCUUUACUAGUCUACCUUAGUGCCAUCCACCAGCUUUACUCUCUGACACACACACGCACACACACACACAAUUUUAACUUGUUUUUUUGUACAUAAUGUACAUACUGUCAAUUUUUUAUUAAAAGAAAUAUGCUUUGAUGUGCUAGCAUAACUGCUCUAGCUUCUUGUGUACCAUAGUACUGUGGCUUCAGAUUUAGUACCUAUGAACAGAUGUACAAGACAUUUAUUACACUUUUUACCAAAGGGAGUUACCAUUGUAGUACUUUUGUGUAAAACUUGUCUUCCCCUUUGCCCCCAACUUUUUUUUUUUUUUUUUUGUAAAUAAAUAAAGCUUGGUUCUUACUUAAGGAAUAAACUCUCAACCCACGUCCCUUGUCCUCACCAGAAAAUACUGUGAAGCAGGGAUUUUGACUUCAGUUCCUUAUCCAGGGUAGAAACAGGAUUUUGCUUAAAAUACUUGUUACUUGUCCCAAAUCAAAAUAUUCCAAAAUCUUAGAAUACUUAAGUCUUUUAGUACGUGUUUUUUUCCCUUGUUCAAAUAAUCUGAAAAUAUUUUAUAUUUGGGUAAGUUGUCAAGCUAUGUAGUUUGUAUUUCUAUAUAUUUUUUCUUAUUCACAUUGGUGAUGGAUGGGGGUGAGCAACUUAAAUACCAAACCAGUGUUUGAAAAAAAAGUGUGCAUAAGGCAUGUGGUAUACCUUAUAAAUGGAGUUGGGAGGGAGAGAAUUUGAAAUGGGAUACCUAUUUUUUUAAUUACAUAAAUUUAAACUAGCAGACAUUUAAACAUGAAUGAUUAGGAUUUUUCUAUGUGGUUAACCUGGACUUUCUGAACAAAGACCAACUGAGCCCCUCCCAGUACUCUGGUGGAUUUUUCUUCAGCAACCAUUACGCAAGUCUUAGUUGUAACCAGCAAUGUUCUGUGUGUUUUAUGUUUGCUUUUUAGUUAAAAAUCACCACCACCACCAAAAAGAAAAACAAAAUUUUUUGGCUCCUGGAUUUUCAAAACACAUGGUAGACCUCUCUGAUUUUAGGCUUUUAUUGUUUAAAGACAGUGUCUCGCUUUAUGACCCACACUGGAGUGCAGUGCCACGAUCAUAGCUCACUGCAGGCUUGACCUCCCAGGCUCAAGCAGUCCUCCCACCUCGGCCUCCUGAGUAGCUGCAUGCCACCACGCCCAGCUAAUUUUUUAACUUUUUGUAGAGACAGGGUCUUGCUAUGCUGCCCAGGUUGGUCUCAAACUCCUGGCCUCAAGCUGUCCUCCCACCUCGGCCUCGCAAAGUGCUGAGAUUACAGGUGUGAGCCACCCUGGCCUGAUUUUAGGCUUUUUUUGUACUGGGGAGAAGAGACUGUGAGCCAAAGUGUAGGGUGCCAAAAAGAGCUUUGUGGGAUGAGAUUUUAGGGCAAAGCUGGGGCAGUGUCUGACUUGGCGGUGGUCAUGUGUACUGAUUUAGGGGAAAGAUCUUGAGGUUUUCUCAAAUAAUUCACCUAUCCCCGUGUUCCCUCAAGAAAGGUCAUGUUGACCUGGAACCAUAGGGGAAAUUGGUGGGGUGUGAUCAGGGUCAGCCCCAGCUGUUGCUGCCCCUGCAGUGUUUUGUCCAGAGCACUUGCCUGCAGGUCAGGAUAGGAUUUCAAGGCCAGUUCAGGAGAAAGUCCCAACCCACCAGUGCAACCAACAAAAGAGUAAGUUUUACCUACAGCCUGGGUUUUCACAAGUAGCAUUUUUAUUCCUCCUGCUGUCUGACAUCUGAGCUCCAAGCUCUAAACCCAACCUGUAUUAUAUGCAGCAGCAGGUUAUCUUUGUUUUAAAUCACAUUUGUUAUUCUGUACUUAGUCACCUUUCCGUGUGAUCUGCAUUUGAAAUGUUGUAAACUUGGUCAGUAUUUCCAUUAAAAUAUCAGGGCUAA